CUUCCUCCCCGCCUCCAGCUGCCGGCAGGACCUUUCUCUCGCUGCCGCUGGGACCCCGUGUCAUCGCCCAGGCCGAGCACGAUGCCCCCUAAAAAGGGAGGUGAUGGAAUUAAACCACCCCCAAUCAUUGGAAGAUUUGGAACCUCACUGAAAAUUGGUAUUGUUGGAUUGCCAAAUGUUGGGAAAUCUACUUUCUUCAAUGUGUUAACCAAUAGUCAGGCUUCAGCAGAAAACUUCCCGUUCUGCACUAUUGAUCCUAAUGAGAGCAGAGUACCUGUGCCAGAUGAAAGGUUUGACUUUCUUUGUCAAUACCACAAACCAGCAAGCAAAAUUCCUGCCUUUCUAAAUGUGGUGGAUAUUGCUGGCCUUGUGAAAGGAGCUCACAAUGGGCAGGGCCUGGGGAAUGCUUUUUUAUCUCAUAUUAGUGCCUGUGAUGGCAUCUUUCAUCUAACACGUGCUUUUGAAGAUGAUGAUAUCACGCACGUUGAAGGAAGUGUAGAUCCUAUUCGAGAUAUAGAAAUAAUACAUGAAGAGCUUCAGCUUAAAGAUGAGGAAAUGAUUGGGCCCAUUAUAGAUAAACUAGAAAAGGUGGCUGUGAGAGGAGGAGAUAAAAAACUAAAACCUGAAUAUGAUAUAAUGUGCAAAGUAAAAUCCUGGGUUAUAGAUCAAAAGAAACCUGUUCGCUUCUAUCAUGAUUGGAAUGACAAAGAGAUUGAAGUGUUGAAUAAACACUUAUUUUUGACUUCAAAACCAAUGGUCUACUUGGUUAAUCUUUCUGAAAAAGACUACAUUAGAAAGAAAAACAAAUGGUUGAUAAAAAUUAAAGAGUGGGUGGACAAGUAUGACCCAGGUGCUUUGGUCAUUCCUUUUAGUGGGGCCUUGGAACUCAAGUUGCAAGAAUUGAGUGCUGAGGAGAGACAGAAGUAUCUGGAAGCGAACAUGACACAAAGUGCUUUGCCAAAGAUCAUUAAGGCUGGGUUUGCAGCACUCCAACUAGAAUACUUUUUCACUGCAGGCCCAGAUGAAGUGCGUGCAUGGACCAUCAGGAAAGGGACUAAGGCUCCUCAGGCUGCAGGAAAGAUUCACACAGAUUUUGAAAAGGGAUUCAUUAUGGCUGAAGUAAUGAAAUACGAAGAUUUUAAAGAGGAAGGUUCUGAAAAUGCAGUCAAGGCUGCUGGAAAGUACAGACAACAAGGCAGAAAUUAUAUUGUUGAAGAUGGAGAUAUUAUCUUCUUCAAAUUUAACACACCUCAACAACCGAAGAAGAAAUAAAAUUUAGUUAUUGCUCAGAUAAACAUACAACUUCCAAAAGGCAUCUGAUUUUUAAAAAAUUAAAAUUUCUGAAAACCAAUGCGACAAAUAAAGUUGGGGAGAUGGGAAUCUUUGACAAACAAAUUAUUUUUAUUUGUUUUAAAAUUAAAAUACUGUGUACCCCCCCCCCCCCAUGAAAUGCAGGUUCACUAAAUGUGAACAGCUUUGCUUUUCACGUGAUUAAGACCCUACUCCAAAUUGUAGAAGCUUUUCAGGAACCAUAUUACUCUCAUGAUACUUCAUUAAUCUCCAUCAUGUAUGCCAAGCCUGACACAUUUGACAGUGAGGACAAUGUGGCUUGCUCCUUUUUGAAUCUACAGAUAAUGCAUGUUUUACAGUACUCCAGAUGUCUACACUCAAUAAAACAUUUGACAAAACCAGCCUUGGUGUGUUUGGGGAUGUCUGUAUUGACUGACUGUGGUGUGCUGAAUGCGAUACGGCACCUGGUGGUUGCUGAUUACAGAAUUUUAAGGCGUGUGUAUGACACAGUAACUGGCAGUGUGGGGCAGCUGCAAUUGUAUCUUAAAAGUGAGUCUUUCAUGGGAAUCAGAAGAAUAGUAUACCAGGGAUUUGUCUCAAAAAAGUUAAUUAAUUUAUAGAUCAACAUUUAUUGAAAGAUGAUAGCAAUGAUAUUAUGAGGGAUAUGAGAUAGGUGACUGACCACAAAGAAGAAAAUUCUGUCUCAAAAAUUAAAGAAUUUUGUUUGUUAUUGUUGUUCUGACCAUAUUGAAAAGAGGUUCACUUUUAAUCUUUCCUUUGAAAUUAUUAAAUUGUAAAAACUGACCCAUUGAUGUCUGGUGGGUUAUGUUUUGCUUCAAUUCAGCAAUGUGUAUAAAAGUUCCUACACUGAUUUUGAAAUACUAAGAUCAGACUUUGAAAAUUUUAAAAAUUCUUUCAUUCUUACUUUUCAGAUAUUUGAGAGCAGUCGAAGUGGUAGUAUGGGUAAGUUAAGCACUUCUUAACAUUGUAGCAGAAAAUUCCAAAAGAAAGACUAGAACAAAUUGGUAAUUUGGAGACCCUUUGCCACUUAGCCUUCUCUUGUGAUGAUGGCCUGAAAGCUCUCUCGGCCCUGAGCCUCCCUUUCUCUCCCAUGUUUCCAUUCCUGUGAGACCUCCCUUCCUUGUCCUUGUCCUCUGCCCUUUUGUGCUCUUCUGUGAUCACAGGACCAUUUCCAUGGAAUGCAGAUUCAUACCCAGCCAGCCUUUGCCUCUACUGUAUCGCUUUGGGACUUUAAAGAUGCAGAAGUAUUAGAACACACACAAACUUAAAAUGGAAAGUUACCAAAUGUAGCACUAGAGGCAAGAAAAGGGGUGAUUUUUUAAAGAUUUGGCUAUACUUAAGAUAUUUAAAGAGGAUGAGGUUGAGUCGUGAGUAUAAUUUAGAAGCUCUCCAGUGAGUAUUUUUUUAGUAUCAAAUAGUGAUCUUCUUUUGCUAACAUAAAAAUGAGUAAACUACAGCAGAGAAAUAAGAAUAAAACUAAUGAAGGGUUUUUUAAAAGAACUAAAUAAAACAAAUAAAACUAGGCUACAGGUAUAGCUGACCAAGUUUGCUGUGAAAAAUCCUUGUUAUAUCUAUUUCUGUAUUGGAGUAAUGUGUAGAUUAGUGGAUUGUUAGGGAUUUCAGCAGUAUAAGAAAGAAUCAAAUAUCUUGCUUUUGGGUCUUCUCCAAAGUAAAUUGCAUGGACUUCUUAAAGAAGUUUGAAAUCAGUAAAAAGACAUUAGGAUCAUGCAAUUUUACUUUGUCUAGCUUCUAAUGUGGUAAAUUGCACAUUGUGCAACAGAACCAUUAAUAAAAGAAAGGAGUUAGUUUUGAGGUAACUGCAUUCAUUAGGGGCUGAAAAUAAAUGUUAAAAAUGUUUAAUUUGGUUAGAAGUUCUACAACAUUGUAUGUACAUAUACAAAAUUUCAUUUUCUCUGAAAGUCGAGAAUUCCAAGAACUGUUACAUAUAAUCAUAUAUAUGCCUAUAUCUAAACGUUUUCCCUCCUUUAAUAUUGAUAAAGUUAAUAUAUUUUAGGAUGUUAUGUAAAUAUUUUUGCAUGUAUCUGUAGCUCCAUCUUAAUCAAAUUUAUGGUUAAAAGAGAUUUGAGGCCAGGCGUGGAGGCUCACACCUAUAAUCCCAACACUUUGGGAGGCCGAGGUGGGAGGAUCACUUGAGCACAGGAGUUUGAGACCAGCCUGUGCAACAUCAUGAAACAUCAUCUCUACAUAAAAAAAUACAUAUAUACAAAAAUUAGCUGGGCAUCAUGGCACACACCUGUAGUCCCAGCUACUUAGGAGGCUGAGAUGGGAGGAUUGAUCGAUCGCUUGAGCCUGGGAGGUGGAGGCUACUGUGAGCCAUGAUCAUGCCACUGCACUCCAGCCUGGGCAACAGAGUGAGACCCUGUCUCCAAAGAGAAAGAGAAACUUGAGAAGGCUUGUGCCCAAAGCUUGAAGAAAGAUUGUAAUAGCAUUUAGUUGUGUUUUAUCAUGUUAUCUUCAUAACAUGCAUUUUGCAUAUGGCUCAGAGCAGAGCCGGAUCUCCCAAGGAAGCACAAAUAGUUUUUGUCGCUAACUUAGUUAUGAGUGAAGCCUCUGUUCACUUAUAACUUGCCAGUUUCAUUGGUGGAAUAAGUCCCCUUACUCAUGAUUCAUCAAUAUUCCUAUAUUAAAAUUCCAGUUUGAUGUUUGUCUCUAGUUGUCUGUGUAUAAUAUUUCCAAAGCUCCUUUGUAAACCCCGUCUCCUUUCAUUCAGAGAGUCAGAGACGGUAUCUCCUCCUCCUGCCUCUUCUAUUGUUCUGAUUAGUCUACUUAAAUUCACUUGAUGCUCUUUUUAUUUUACAAGAGACUUGAGAAAUGUCGGUUGUUCCUAAUGGCAAACUACUUUAGCUGGGAAAAUUCAUUUCAACUUAUUUUAAGCUUGUAAAAUACACUGUGGUGAUAAAAUAAAAGAGCUGGGUUUGA